AGUCACAGCAGCAAGCAAGUCUAGUGAACAGAUAAGAUGACAUGCUCAGCAAAAUAACAACGAAACCAGAGGUAAGCAUUUAAUAAACACAUAUGGAAUUAAUCUAAAGGUUUUUUUUUUUAAUCUUCAAGAAUUCUGCUAUCAUAAUCUUUCAUUUCUAUUCAGCGGUUUAAAAAUCAAAAUGAAAAAUUUACUAAUGCUAAAGGAGAGUUUUUAAAAACGUGAUUUGUACAUUUGAUGAACAAAUAAAUGGUCUAAUCUUCCUUUUGGUUUCCCUUUCUUCUCAAGGCAACUGGGAAGGUUAAAAAAAUAAACACUACUUAAAACAAAAAAAGAACUGGUUUGAAUUUGGCAAAUUUAGUGAUUAAAUUUAGAACACAAUUGUUGCAAAGACAUACCAUGAGAGAUGAAAUUACUAAACACAAUUAUUUGGAUCCUAGUAAUACCUUUUUUUUUCCUUCUCUCAAACUAAAGGAAAUCUAAAAUGACAUUUAUAUCAGUACUCACAAACCUGAUAAGACAAAGCUAAUUACAUAUAAGGAUCCCUAGCUGGUAAAACAUUUAUUUAGACCCUUGUUGGGCUUUGAGUGUUUCUAGGUGGGUGGCCAGCGCAUACUAAAAGUUCUAUUCUGAACUAUUGUGUUUCGACUUUUCUAUUCUUCUGUAAGUAAAGGUAAAAAGACAUUCAAGGGUCAGGAAACACCUAACUUUUUAUUAUAACCAUUGAAAAAAUUAAUGUGUCUUCUGUUUCAUUAACUGAGCAACAUCAGAAAUACAGUAUAUUUGGAGAAUUGGCUGCAUUGUCACAAAUGCACAACAGACUUACUAAGAAGGGAAGGGCUAUGAAGUUCAAGUGUUUUUACCACUUUCAGAAAUGAAUAAAAUAAUGCAGUCUAUGUAUUUUGUAUCUAGGGGGAACUCUCUGGCAUGCAAGUUCAAACACGACUCUACAACUACGGCAGAAAAAGAGAGAGAGAGAAACUAAAAAUAUAUAUAUAUCCUAUUUUUUUCACAGCUAUCAGUUUCUUUCACUGAGCUUUCCUAAAUUUAAGCCUCUAGAAAAUAAUAAAUACUUGGAUAUCUUACCUACAAACAUGGACAGAUGUGUGUAUGCGCUCAUUUUAGAGAACUUGAAUUUUUUUUUUUAAAGGAAGGUGUCAACUUUGGCUUUUGAGUGUUUGGCAUGGUUACAAUGCCUUAAAAAAACAGAUGAGCAGCUUAGCUACUAACCAUGCUGACCACUGUUCGGAACGGGAUUGAAUCACAGAAAAACAGCAAAUGGCUCUCUCUUACAGAGUGUCUGAACUUCAAAGCACAAUUCCUGAGCACAUUUUGCAGAGCACCUUUGUUCACGUUAUCUCUUCUAACUGGUCUGGAUUACAGACAGAAUCAAUACCAGAGGAAAUGAAACAGAUUGUUGAGGAACAGGGAAAUAAACUGCACUGGGCAGCUCUUCUGAUACUCAUGGUGAUAAUACCCACAAUUGGUGGAAAUACCCUUGUUAUUCUGGCUGUUUCACUGGAGAAGAAGCUGCAGUAUGCUACUAAUUACUUUCUAAUGUCCUUGGCGGUGGCUGAUUUGCUGGUUGGAUUGUUUGUGAUGCCAAUUGCCCUCUUGACAAUAAUGUUUGAGGCUAUGUGGCCCCUCCCACUUGUUCUAUGUCCUGCCUGGUUAUUUCUUGACGUUCUCUUUUCAACCGCAUCCAUCAUGCAUCUCUGUGCCAUUUCAGUGGAUCGUUACAUAGCCAUCAAAAAGCCAAUCCAGGCCAAUCAAUAUAACUCACGGGCUACAGCAUUCAUCAAGAUUACAGUGGUGUGGUUAAUUUCAAUAGGCAUUGCCAUUCCAGUCCCUAUUAAAGGGAUAGAGACUGAUGUGGACAACCCAAACAAUAUCACUUGUGUGCUGACAAAGGAACGUUUUGGCGAUUUCAUGCUCUUUGGCUCACUGGCUGCCUUCUUCACACCUCUUGCAAUUAUGAUUGUCACCUACUUUCUCACUAUCCAUGCUUUACAGAAGAAGGCUUACUUAGUCAAAAACAAGCCACCUCAACGCCUAACAUGGUUGACUGUGUCUACAGUUUUCCAAAGGGAUGAAACACCUUGCUCGUCACCGGAAAAGGUGGCAAUGCUGGAUGGUUCUCGAAAGGACAAGGCUCUGCCCAACUCAGGUGAUGAAACACUUAUGCGAAGAACAUCCACAAUUGGGAAAAAGUCAGUGCAGACCAUUUCCAACGAACAGAGAGCCUCAAAGGUCCUAGGGAUUGUGUUUUUCCUCUUUUUGCUUAUGUGGUGUCCCUUCUUUAUUACAAAUAUAACUUUAGUUUUAUGUGAUUCCUGUAACCAAACUACUCUCCAAAUGCUCCUGGAGAUAUUUGUGUGGAUAGGCUAUGUUUCCUCAGGAGUGAAUCCUUUGGUCUACACCCUCUUCAAUAAGACAUUUCGGGAUGCAUUUGGCCGAUAUAUCACCUGCAAUUACCGGGCCACAAAGUCAGUAAAAACUCUCAGAAAACGCUCCAGUAAGAUCUACUUCCGGAAUCCAAUGGCAGAGAACUCUAAGUUUUUCAAGAAACAUGGAAUUCGAAAUGGGAUUAACCCUGCCAUGUACCAGAGUCCAAUGAGGCUCCGAAGUUCAACCAUUCAGUCUUCAUCAAUCAUUCUACUAGAUACGCUUCUCCUCACUGAAAAUGAAGGUGACAAAACUGAAGAGCAAGUUAGUUAUGUAUAGCAGAACUGGCAGUUGUCAUCAAACAUAAUGAUGAGUAAGAUGAUGAAUGAGAUGUAAAUGUGCCAAGAAUAUAUUAUAUAAAGAAUUUUAUGUCAUAUAUCAAAUCAUCUCUUUAACCUAAGAUGUAAGUAUUAAGAAUAUCUAAUUUUCCUAAUUUGGACAAGAUUAUUCCAUGAGGAAAAUAAUUUUAUAUAGCUACAAAUGAAAACAAUCCAGCACUCUGGUUAAAUUUUAAGGUAUUCGAAUGAAAUAAAGUCAAAUCAAUAAAUUUCAGGCUUUAAAAAGAA